AGAAGCCAAAGCCUGCGGGUGACUCAGGUGCCUGAGGGAGUUUCGGGAGCAGAGGGCAGCCAUCUCAGAACUGAUUCUGGAGGAAGUGGGAUCAGAGGCCAAAGGCAGAAGGUGGAAGGGGGCUUCAUGAGUCAUCUGCCCUCAGCCUGGGCCAGGUGUAGGGGAGAUCUUUGUGCCAGCCACCCUAGAGUAGAUCUGGGUGGAAGAUGACUGGAUUCAACACCCCCAGGGCUGGAAGGAUCUGUGGGGUUGAAGGAGCUGAGUCUGUCAGUCCUUCCUGGUUAGGGGUUGGAGGCUCUGCCUCCACAGUCCAGGCUGAGGCAGAGGCCUGCCUCUCCUUCCAGAGAAGUCGGGUGGAAGGGAGAAAUGGCAGUCUCUAAGACUCCGAGCGUACCUGGCUAACUUCCAUAGUGCCCAGAGAAGGAGCUCAGUCGGCAAGGACUAGCCGAGGAUCCCAGUCCUAGCAGCCUCCUGUCCCCUGCUCAUGUGUCUAACAGCCUUUAACCUUCUCAGCACCUAGGAACCCAGGCAGCCUGGGACUAUCUGAUCCACUUGUUCUAAAACACAGCCAGCAGGUCCAUGGCCAGCAGGCCUCUGCCCCCGGGACGCCAGGAGGAGGAGAAUGCCAAAGACUCCGGGCGGAAACCCUCACCGGUGCGGCCCCGAGGCUGCCUGCCCAGCAUUGAUGAGGCCCGACCGGCAGGUCCAGGUCCAGCCCCGGCCUCGCGCCGGGGCUCCAUGCUGGGCCUGGCCGCGUCCUUCUCCCGCCGCAACUCGCUGGUCGGGCCAGGCGCGGGUCCUGGGGGUCAGCGGCCAUCCCUGGGCCCGGUGCCCCCUCUGGGCUCAAGGGUCAGCUUCUCAGGGUUGCCCCUGGCGCCCGCCCGUUGGGUGGCGCCCUCCUACCGCACGGAGCCAGUGCCCGGGGAGCGCUGGGAGGCUGCGCGUGCACAGCGUGCCCUGGAGGCGGCGCUGGCCGCAGGGCUGCACGACGCGUGCUACUCCAGCGACGAGGCCGCGCGGCUGGUGCGGGAGCUCUGCGAGCAGGUGCACGUUCGCCUGCGCGAGCUCAGCCCGCCACGCUACAAGCUGGUAUGCAGUGUGGUGCUGGGGCCGCGCGCGGGCCAGGGCGUUCACGUGGUCAGCCGUGCGCUCUGGGACGUGGCGCGCGAUGGGCUGGCCUCGGUCUCCUACACCAACACCUCGCUCUUCGCGGUGGCCACGGUCCACGGGCUCUACUGCGAGUGAGGGGGAGUCCAAUUCUGCAAAAUUGUUUAUUAUCCUAGGAGGAGGCCCCCCUGGGGCUCACAUCCCAAUAAAUAAGUGUCUGACAAUAAAUAAAAGUGGUCCAUAAAUAA